AUUGAUGCGCAUGCGCAGGGCUUCAGCCUGCACGUACUCGGAUUGUGCAGCGACUCCCCGUGGCGGUUGAGGGGCAGUGGUGGCGGCGGAAGCCCAAGUCGAUGCUGAUGUUGAUGCUGGUGGCGGCUGUGACCAUGUGGCUCCGACCGCUGGUCACAGCUCAGCUCUGUCGUUCUCGCACAGUGAGGACAGGAAAAGUGUUUAAUCUGAUACAGGACGUUCAAGGGGACCGCCUGUAUUUUCAUCCUACAACAACACGCUUGAUUAAACAUCCUUGCGAGAAAAAUAUAGCACUAUAUCUAGGGAAACAAGUUUUUUUCACAAUGGAUAACUUUGAGACUAGUCUCCUUCCAUUUACCAUCCCUACAUCAAUGCAGGUCGGCGUACCAGAAGUGACAUCAGCACAUUUUGCUGGUUCGUUAUUGCUGUUAGUAGUGGAUCAAAAAGUCUAUAUUUAUGAUUAUGAAAAUAAUUCUUGGAGCAUGUCUUUAGGUAUAAAACACCCUGUUACACAUGUCUCUGGUGAUAAUUGUUGUUAUACUGGAAGUUUGUUUUGUGUGCAUGUCAGUAAUUUGGUUUUUGCAUAUUUCCGUGGAGAUCAGAUAUCCCAGACUUAUAUAUAUUAUUCAAAUACUGGGGGAUUCAGUUUUUGGAAGUAUCACUAUGACAGACAGGCAGAAAUCAUUGGGUCUUUAGGCGGAAUCUUCCACUUUUUUUCUUUGUCACAGGUUGCGAUGCUUGUAGUGAAUCAAGGGAAGGGCAUGUUCAAGUACUCAGAUCACCCCCUCAACCGGAGUUUCGGGCUGUCUUUUGACUAUAAUGGGACUCUAGACAUCCUCAUCGCCCCCGGCCAGAGAGGCAUCCUGCUCCUAUGGUUUGAGAACAGCCUGUUGUUUUCCCAUAAUGCAGGUCAGCUCGUCGACACCGUCCGGGUGAAAAAAGGAGACCAGACCUUGUUUUCUUCCAUUUUUGAAGCCAAGAUCACCAUCCACAACAUUGCUGUCACUGAAAAUGAACUGGCAGUUAUAACUCGGGAGGAUAAUUUGUAUUAUGGCAAUCUGGGCAUCGUGCCAAGUUCCAUAAUCAAAUUUGCAGACCAAUACAUCUGGUCAGAAGACGUGGCCCUGAUGUUCAGGAGCCCAGGGACUCUGGAAAUACUGACCCCACUGCGUGACACAGCCUUUCCAGCUUUUGAUUUCCAGAAGUGCCUCGUGAAUAUCCAGGCGCUUCUCAUGGACCCUGAACUCCACGUUGGAAAGUGCAAGAUAGAGUUUCUGACAGGAGAAUUUAUAUACAGGAUGUAUACCAUUGACAUGCACAGCCAGCUGGAAUUGACUGCUUCGUUGAUACCCCAGCCAGGCACAUCCCUGAUUCCUCUGGUGAUGGUGAGCAACCCCCACUCCCUGGGGUUCCAGGCCACCUUCUACGAGAACGGUUACACAUCAGAUGGGAACACCAAGUACAAACUGGAUAUUUUCCUAAAACAGCAGCAGCACUGGGGCAGGACCGACUCCAACUUCACUUCCAGUUUAAAGAAAGCCACCAUGUCUACCUUAACUGUGGACAUAGCAAACAAGGAAAUUUCAUGUGUGGAUAUCAAGCCACUGUCGACACUGAUUUCAGUUGGCUGCGACCUGGAUAAAAAGAUCGUCAUCCAGAACAAAGUUUCCGCCUGUUCCAUGGGCAUCCUGGACCCCUUGACCCUGCAAGACAAUUACAGCUUCAUCAUCGAGAAGGAAUUCUACGACCCCGGCUUCCAGGGGCAGCAGUCCUCCGAGGACCUGCACGUGUUUUACUCCUACCAGCAGCUGGGCUGUCCUCUCCUCGUCUACUAUGACACCCUAUGGAAGCCCGUGGUGGAGCUGUGGCGAAAAGACAGUUUCCAGGAGGUCAUCGACGCCGAGUAUGUGUUACUGGAGGUGAACGGGCAGUUCUCAUACUCCUAUUCCCUGACGGCCCAGUCGGCCAUGUGUACCUCCCAGCCGCAGAACUGGACCACCAUGAUAAAGGAAUUCGGGGGGCCCUUCUUCUGGAACAGAGAGGCUUCAGAUGUACCAAAUCAGAAGAAACACUGUGCCUGGCUCGUGACCGCCCUCAGCAUUCCUUCUGGGCGGCAGACGCAGUUUGUCAGUUUGCCAACAUUCUGCUUUUAUGAGAAAGUUUGCUGUUUACUCAUAUGGCCUCCAGUGGUAUACGGAGUUGAUCACCACCCUCAAUCUUUCGGCCUCCAACAGAGGCAGAACUAUGUGAGCUGCCACGACCCCAACAACAAUGCCCCUUUGAGGUGGCCAGACGUCCAGUAUCAGAUCUUGGGCGGCCGGACAGCAAACCAGAUCAUUUUCGGCCACAAUGGCUUUUAUGUCUUCUACAUUUCGAUCGUGGAUCCGUACUACAGCUACUGUCAACUGGAGACCAUCUUUAGCAUCUACGUGUAUGGAGCAUUCCCCGUGCAGCUGGUCUCUGCUGGAGUCGUCAUCCUACUGAUCAUCUCCAGCAUCCUGGGGUCCGUUUGGCUGGCCUACAAGACCCCCAAGCUGCUACGCACAGCACGCGGCCGCAGGAUCAAGAAGUGUGCGACACAGCUGUGUAGGAGAUGCAAGACGGUCUGCCAGUUCAGGGCCUCAGCCACAGCCAGGGCAGGCACAGAGCCCCCGGGACGCCACCGCACUCCUCACGGAGGCAGGUCUGACCACUGAGGCCGGUCCACAGGGUCCCAACCCCUUGUCUUCAAAUAAAGUAUAAUGUAACAUAGCA